GGCAGCUCCUGGAGCCCAAAGUCAAGAGCGAGAGUCUGCAUCUUGCUGGUUCAUGCUCAGGGCUCCAGGCUGAUGUCCCCACUGCUUGGAUAAAGAGCCGCUCCCUGUGACCUCAGCAUUCUACUACCCAAAAAUAUGCCACAGGGAGAGGGAGCCAGUGAUAAAGAGAUGCCAGGAGUGGGGGAGGAGAGGUGCCUCUGGAGUAAAUAGGAGAGAAAAUGGGUGCGUUUUGCUUAUCUACAGCCCAGGGCUCCCGCCCGGACCCCUCUCCUGCUGUUGGUCUGUGCUGGGGAGCUGCACGCGCUCUGGGCCCCUGCGCCAGAAGCAGCGGUGAAGCGGUUUACUUUGACCUUGUCUGCUUAGGCGCUGAAAUUCUGCGGAAGCAUCCCGAGGUGAAACUGCAAGAGUGGGAAUGAACUUUGGGGGAGCCCUGCCUUGGCUGGGAAGCCAAACGAUCAUUUCAGAAGACUACAGCUCAGGAUAGCACAGGGUAGACGUCUGUGCACUUGAACGCUCCCCCCUCAACGAGGACUUGCUAGAGGGUUACCUUUCCAUGCCUUAUCUCAGUGGGGGGACUGUCAGAGUGACUGCGCUGGCUGGGUACUUGAUGAAAAAAUACCACUCACAAGACCCGGGCCAUUCCCAGAGUAGUACAUACAUGAAAAUGAUAUAACCCUUAUUAAGCUUACGCUACAGCAAGUUACCGUCAUUUCACUAUGCAGAGGCGGAAAGUGCUGGUUUUUACUAUUCCCCCACACUGUACUAUUUCUUACAUUCAUAUCCUGUUGAAUGUUACUUUUGAAAGUUCAUAUUUAUCUUUGCAAUUUUUUUGCAAGAAUGAUUAGCAAACAUGCACAAGGAGCUCAAAGAAAAAAUGGAAGUCCUGCCAUCUGCAUGCCUCACCAGAUAUUAAUCAUUUACUAUCCAUGUUUACUACUUACAUUAGAUGGCACUGCUCCUCACGAUGGUUUUAUUAGAGGCGCAUUUGGUUAAGGAAAAGAAAAAGUCUAGCACAGCUAUCACUAAUUGCAUGAUUUUGCAUAAAUUACAUUAGCCAUGGAGAGUUUUGUUUUCUUCACUAAAUUCAUCAUUUUGUUUAAAAGACUAAACAAUUCAGUUUAAUUUCUUUAGCUAAAUGAAAGACUUUUCCUUAAAGACAAGAUGUCCUUGAAAAGCUACAUAUGUCUUUAAACUUAUUACAGUUGCCACGACUUUGUAUUUUAUCAUUGUGAUUAAGACUUUGAGCUUUCAUGUAAGUCAGGCCCUUUAUCCUAUUAAGAAACAGAAUUACUGGUUAAGAAAUAGGCUAACAAGGCAAAAGCUGGGAAGCUCCAUGUCUGCACAAUGAGAUUUCUGCAAGCUCUAUGGGAGGCUGGGUACUCUAUUACUCUGUUUACUUCGGGGGCUUCUCUGUUUUGCCACAGUUGUUUUCCCCUGUGGCAGGAAAGGGAAUUUUUGUGUUUUGUUUCUCCCUCUGUAGGGAAAAAUUUUUAAAUAAAUCAAUAAAUAAGAGAAAGACUUGUACGUGAAAGGCAUUCAUCUACAAGGAAGACUCCUACACACUGAAAUAAGCAGUCCAAAAAUCAAAAUGAUUCUCAGAAAUAACAACGGAUCGCAGUGGAGUGGCAGGACAGACCCGUUCACGUAGACAUUUGUAUUCUCUUGUUUGCGCCCAGCCAUGGCUAUCUCAUUUAGAGACAACUACUGAACUCUGGAAUAUGAGAAGCAGGUGACUUAUGCUUCUCAGAGACUCAUGAUACAGAAAUGAUCACAGCUACCUCCCAAAGCAGCAGCUCUGUGGUCAGAUAUUUACGUAGGAGGGCAGUGACAGGUUCACCACGGAUUUUAACGCUUGUGAAGGAUGCUGUUCAACGCGUCCAUAGCAUCCAAGAAGCUCAGUUGGGAAGGCAGGCAAAUUCUACAUACUUGAGGCAAACCACCGUCAUUCUGGGAGUGUGAGGUCAUAAAAACUCCCCAGAUAAAACCAGUGUCAUCGUCAUUUUCAACAGUCUUUCAUAAAUGUGAAGCACCACAACCCCUCCCCACCAUGAUUCCACUGGUUGGAGACCUACAUUCCCCAACCAGAAAUUAGCUGGCAUGAUUUAUGAAGCAGAUCCUUUUUUGUCUCACAUAUUUGAUUUUAAUAUUUCAUAACAUUAUGGGGUGACUUCAAUAUUUUAAAGCAAAAUUUAAUAUGAUUGAUACUACAUGACGACACUUUCAUUACCAUGAAAUUCUCAUACAAACAUUGAGAGAAGUCUUUAUUCCAAUACUGGAGCUAACCUAUGAUAUAUAUGUAGUGAAACUUCAUGACUUUUAAUCAGUUUAUUUAAAAUGUACAUUGUUCUUAUACAUUAAGGACAGAAUACAGACUUGCAGGAACCAAACUAUAGGGACCCUGACAGGAUUGCUGUAAACAAGUUGUUUGGACAAUGUCUUGUGUUAAGCACUAAGCCAUGAAAGGAUAGGUUUGAACCUUUGGACCAUGUGUGAUAAUGUGUCUGUUUCAGAUCCUGAAGGCACUAACUAAGGUAUCUCCAGGCAACCAAGGAUCUUACCUCUCACAUUGAGAAAAACCAUAACUUCAGAGACAUUUCCUGGCUCCAAAUUCAAGUCCUUUCAGAGACCCCUCUACUGUAAGUCACAGGAUAUUCAGUGUGCAUUUGAGUCGUACGUGCUUUAGACAUUAUUCAAACCAUAAUGAAUGGGUUGAGGGACUUUGAGGUGUAUAAAGAUGUUAUCAGAUGACAAAUCACUACCUGAAUAAAAACAAAACAUUCUAACCUGACAAAUGUGUCUCUUUCUGCUGAGUAUGUAUUCCCAGCUCUAAUUGGGACUGAGAGAAAAUUAACUUGAAUGUAGAACAGCAGAUAUUAGGGACAAGCAGGAAUUAUGAUUCUAAAUUACUCUAUAAACCUUUUGGCUAACAACAUAUUUCAAAGGGAUUUGGAAAUAACUCUCCCCAAAGUCAUUAUUUGUGAAUAUUUAUUUUAUAGAGCACUGAACUGUUUAUUCAAAGUAUUGCACAUCCAUAGACAUGUUCUCUUUACCACACUAUCCUGCUGUUAGGAAGUUUGAGCAAAAAAAGAAAAGAAGAGAGUCUUACAUCUCUGCACAGCAUACAUUCAUAUGAAUUAUACUAUUCUAUCCAAUAGAAUGGUAAAGAAACAAAAGAAAACCCCACCAUAUCAAAAUGCUUGUUGAAGUUUAUAUUCUACUUAAUAUGGAAAAUUCCAGUUCAGCCCUUAAUAAUCUAGCUUUGGCCAUGAAAUGAAAUGCAGUAAACUACAACAUAUGAGAGACAUGGGAAGGAGGCUACGGAAUGCUGAAAAUACUACAGGCAGCCUUGCAAAUAAAAGUUGCUCUCACUCCAUCUCAGCAGAGAUGAUCACAGCUAUAUCCCAAAGCAGGGGUUCCAUGGACAGGCACAUCCCAGAGAGAAAGAGGAAAAAGCACAGGCUGAUGGCAUGAGGGCCUUUUUACAGCUGUUCAGUUGAGGAAGCAGCAUGGGGCUAUAUCCUAUUCACUGCCAACCUUAAUGAAAUUGAGCAGUCUUUGUGUUUCUAGGUCAUUCCACUGGUGAUGUGAGAUCCCCCACCCUUGUUCUUCUCUAGGAAGGAUCUUGUAUUUGUCAAUGGUCCUUCUUCAUGUUUUUAAAAAUCUUUUCUAUGUGUACUUAGUGGUUACAUUUUAGAUACCUCUUACUACCUGCAUUUUGUACAGUGAAAUCUGCUUAUUUUUGUAGUAAGUGAUUUUAGCAUCCUUAAAAAAUGCAGCAAAGAUAUAAAACCUGGGAUUUUUAAAUGGGGCAAGCAUAGGGAAGGUAGAUGGAUAUGCAGAUGGCUUUGUUCAGAGAGGACUUCUGAUUUGUGGAUAUGUACUGAGCUGUUGCAGCAGUGGCCAAGGCAAUGUGUAAGGUGUUACAAGACCAAGUGAGAGGACUCCAAGAAGCUCAAGUCCAGGAGGAGGGGAGGAGGUGGCAAGGAAGUGGCAGGAGCCUAAAGACUCCCAGGUAGAAUCAGGAUAGGAGAUUACAGGCAGAGAGUGAUGCCCCGGCUCACUUCGUGGGUGAUGCUUGAGAUUGCACUCCUGAGCCCAGCAGACAUUAGUCCUGGAGCUUAAGCCAAGUGGUAGGGUGCUCAGGGCUACAGACUUGUAUGGGAAGAGUGAGAAGUGACAUUCAGCAAAGGUUGAGGUGCUGGAAUCAGAGAGUGGAGGCAUAGUCUGGAGUCAGUUUGAGGAGGAACCAGCAGGGCAAGAGGGUCCUCUGUUGAUGUUUGAAACAAGAACAUAUAUUCUCAGAAGAUUAAGGCGGUAUAACUAGAGGCAAACCAGAGGAGAGGAGUUGGAGACCAGUUGAGAAGGUGUCACAGAUGAGAAUGUGCCAGUCUCAGUAGCACUGGGAAGUAAGUUAGGGGGCAGCUAUGAGUAAAACCUUCUGGCAGACAAGUCUUUGUAAUGUGGCAAGAUAGAAAGAAGGGAUUAAAGAUGCUACCCAAGGCCAGCAAGGCGGUGGGGGAUUUUAAUGGCAACAGAAAUCUGGGAGCCAGCAGGAACGGGGGGGGGGGGGGGGGGAAGAUAGGAUUUCUAUUAAAUAUUUGAGUGUGAAUUUUCAACUGGAAAUAUUAUUUAAAAAAUAAGUUUUUCAUUAUCUCUUACGUCCUAGAAUGUCCACAAGAAAUACUUUGAAAUAGGAGGAAAUUGGAUGAAGCGAUUCACAGCGCAAAUCCUUAAAUGACUAAGCAUAGUAGUAUCUAUAACAGGUGCUUAAUAAAUAUUUAAUGAGGCUACUAACACAAACCUAGCCAGUGAUUUUGCUACCAACUCAGGGAAUCCUGAUUGGGAAAGAAUUGUUUUCUUCCAUUUCCACUUGUAACUUUUUGUGUAGCAGGAAUUAAAGGAAACACCGUGAGAAGGCAGUAAAGAGGAAGACGGCUUCCAGGGCUGAACAGUACUGACGUCUGGCCAUGCAGUGUUUAGAAAAGAAAAAAGCACCAAAGGGUUGGGUUCUUUACCACCAAACUCAACCUCAGCGAUUCCUUUGGUGAAAAUUCAGUUGGGUAGAAGUUGAGUUUUUAGAGAAAGAAUGUCUUUGAAUUUGGUGACCUAGUAUUAGGGUAAAAGAAGCAAAUAAGGAGAAUUGAGAAAAUGUAUCUCACUGCAGUCAGAUAAAUUAAUGUUCUUAUAACCCAAAUGCUGACAUUCUGGGUUAAAAAGAGUUUUCACCAGAGCUCACCAAAAAAACUGGAGAGUUCAUCGGGCCAGCAUGAGAGAAGGAGAUGUCUGUCUCUCAGCCUUAACCUCACAUCUCAAUUUGACGUCGUGACUUCAACUCCAUUGAUCUCUGUGCCAGACCCACCAAUUUAUCAUUUUAAAAAUCAAUGACAGCGCUGCAUAAAGAUUAUUUUUGUCUUUUUUUCCUUGCGUAAAUCACACUGCACAGUGUCCACUUAACCGUGCACUUGAGACUCCCAUAGCUUAGAUAAUGUGCCAUGUGCAAACGUACUGUGUGAACUUAAAGGAAUGCUGAAAAUAUGCUGUUCACUUUCAAACCGUAUUUUUCAUUUGACUUCUUGCCCAAUGAUAACUGCAUUUCUCAAUUACUUACUGUUUUAGUUUUAAAGGUAGUUGUUAGCUCAGUGGCUUCACUGAAGUCAUUCAUAUCCUCAUUUAAUUUGUUUUGCACUUGCUAUUUAUAUUUUAGUCUUGCUAUAUAAUAUUUAUUCUGAAUAUAUAUCUACUUUAUUUAUUGUGUCUAUCACAUUUGUCCAUGUGGCAAAAACACCCAGGGUGAGGCUGAAUGACAGAAGUUAGCAGGUGGCUGGACACUGGAGCCUCAGACAGAGUGCCCAGGCUCACUGGCAGGGUUGGCCCCACACUGCACUGGGCAGGUCAACUACUGAGUGAGUGGCAGAGACUGGACCCCAACUCACUCCUAGUAAUUAUUUAAAAUAAUUCCACAUGGAAGCAUCAGUUCUAACUGUAUCUGAAGAGUCAGUGAGAGUGACCACUAGCAAAUGCAGCUUUAAAGUAUAAGUCUAAGACAACCGUACAGUUUUUAAUCAGCCACUCAAGGUUGGAACCUUCUGGUGGUGAUUCUCAAGCUUGUGUCUCGUAGGUCCUGCAUCCAGUGUCAUCCACAUGCACAACACAUCCCAAGGUGUGCUGUCUUUGUGUACAUCCACUUCAUCACCAGGGCUGUGUACUGAGCGCUUCCUAGGAGCCGACCACCUGAGCCCUGACCCAGCUCACAGUGGAGUGCAGCGUGGUGGUGCGGUAACAGGCUCCAGGCCAGGCUGUCCUCCUUUGCCCUCCUGGCUCUGCCAGUAUCUGUGUGACCUUUGGCAUGUGACUCCACUACCUGUGCCUCUGUUUCCCCAUCUUUAUUACAAAUAGUAAUUUCUCCUUCAGAGGGUGUUUGGAGAAUGAAAGGUUCAGACAUACACAAAGCACAGAACGGUACCUAGCUUGUGCUGAGUGUUAUACACAAGUGUUACCUUUUCUGAUCUUUGCUCUCCCAGGUUAGAUCACUUGCCCAGAGUUCUGGGCUAUUAAGUGGAGGGGAAGGGCCAGAACUCAAAUCCAAGCAGGUGGUCUCAAAGCCCCAGUUCGUAAGGACUACGGCCAGAAAUUAACCACGUUAGCAAACCAUGGUAGCAUGGGAAGACCUUGAGCACCCCCUCUCUAAUGCAGAAAUUCCAGAGUUAUUCACUGUGCAAAGACUGUCAAUGUACGAAUGACUGGUCUCAAACCCCAGAUCCAUGGUUGAAAAGAGCUGCCCCAAGCCAUGGAAUUUCUAGAAGGGAACAGAAUUCUAAAUGUUUUGCGUCUCCAACCAGAAAUAUAUAUACAUAAAAAAAAGUGUGAAUAUGCCCUAUUCCUACUAUGGGUCUGCUCAGUGACAAUUUACUUGGAAUUUGCCAUCCCAUAAUUAAUGGAUGUUGUGAAAGACCUGGAUUUUCAUCCAUGACAAUAACUGGCCACUAGCUCUCUCCUCUGUGGAACAUGAAUCCACCCCAUCUGUUUGUGCACAGCACAGCCCAGCCAGGCCAGGGCACAGACACUCUGUGGGCCUGUGUGGGAUCUGCUGGUGAUCAUCCCAACACCUGGCUGAUGUCCAGGUUCAUUCUAGAAAAAAAUGGAAGGGGCUCAACCUCCCUGCUCCCCCGUGACAUUCACUCAUUCAUUAAGCCCUUCGUUCAGUCAAUAUUUCUGGGUACUUUUUGUAUGCCACAAACUUCUCUAAGCUUUGGAGAUACAGCAGGAAAUAGAAGACAACAAAGGGUGAAAAAGAUAAAGGAAGAAGGCCAGUGGUUCUUUAUCGUAUGUGCAUUAUUAAAAUUAUAUUAGGCAUUUAAAACAAACAGUGGAACCCAGUCUCCAUCCUCCAGAAGUUCUGAUUUACCUGGACUGGGGUAGAGACCAAUAUGCUUUUGCUUUUGCUUGCUUGCUUGCUUGCUUUUCUCUCUCUUUUCUUUCUUUCUCUCUUUCUCUCUUUCUUUCUUUCUUUCUCUCUUUCUUCUCCUUGUUUUUUAAUGGAUUAACUUCCUGGCCUCCAAGUGUGGCCUUCGAGGGAGCGAGGCUGAGGGAAUAGAGCCCUUAAGGAAAAAUGCUUGUUUACCUCCUUCCUGUAGGAGGACAGCCACCCCCUGGAUUUUCUUCUACGUGGCAGGAUAUGCUCUCUUUAAAAACCCACACACAAAAACAAAAACCAAAACAACUUUUAAAAGACUCCAUUUCAUCCACACCUAUGCUCUCCUCCAAAGCUUCAAGAAGGCGAAAGCAUACAGGGGUCAUGUGAGGUUUUGGAAAGAUUUAUGUUUUCCUUUUUCAAGAUCUUUUUAGCAUGCUCAAGUCCACAGAGAAUCAUUUCACAGAUCAUCAGUACUGCUUACUCACUACGAUGCUAACUUCUAUUCAUGAACUACACAGGCUUUUGCUACUGUUCUCUUUCUCUUUUCCACAAGCCUUGUAAAGUAGCAGGGCAUCUGUUCCAAGGAGGUGCUGGAGAGAUAAAAAGAUAGAGGCAAACGCAGGAAUAUUUGCUGAAAAUGGGACUCUUCAUUGAGUUUAACACUUAAUGUGUUAUGUGUUGGGUGCUUCAUAGAACAGGAAACUGUAUGAUGUCCUGCUUUGGGUGCCUGCCCGAGCCUGGGCUCUUGUUUUGCCCCGGGGUGAAUUGUCACGUUCCCUUCUGGACAGGAGAUGGGGUUGCUGCAACUGGCCCUUUAAGAGCAACCAAAACGCUGGGAGUCAUGGCUGAAGGCUAUCAAAACUCUAUGUGCCUGAUUCAAGGAACAGCCCACAGAUGUCCCACAGCUGACCUGGACUUAUGUUCCAGCACACAUCCCCUUCCCCUCCUGUAUCUGUGUGUGCAUGUGUCUGUUUGUCUGUGCAUUUCUCUCGACUCACCGUUCCCCUAACAACCUCUCUCUCUUUAUACAUCCCCAUUGCCCUUCUCCUUCCUCUCCACGUUCAUCUCAAUGGACAACAGCAGUGUGGCAUGAGAUUCCUAAGUACUGCGCUUCCUUAUUUAGUAUAAUUUUAUAUUCAUUGUUCUCAGUCUAAAGAACAGGAAAAUGAAAGCUAUUUCAUUCAUAUGUUUAUGCCCCUCUGAUACGGUUUGGCUCUCUGUCCCCACCCAAAUCUCACCUCCAAUUGUAAUCUCCAUAAUCCCCAUGUGUCAAGGGUGGAACUGGGUGGAGGUAACUGGAUCGGGGGGGGGCGGGGGGGCGGUUUCUCCCAUGCUGUUAUCAUGAUUGUGAGUGAAAUCGCAGGAGAUCUGAUGGUUGUCUAUCGGAUGUGUUAAGGAGAGCCUCCCAAGUAGCUGGGAUUACAGGCACGCACCACCAUGUCUAGUGUCUGGCAUUUCCCCUGCUUGCGCUCAUUCAGUCCUGCAGCCUUGUGAAGAAGGUGCCUGCUUCUCCUUUGCCUUCUGCCAUGAUUUUAAGUUUCUUGAGGCCUCCCCAGCAAUGCAGAACGGAGAGUCCGUUAAACACCUGUCCUUUAUAAAUAACCCAGUCUCAGGCAUUUCUUCAUAGCAGUGUGAGAAUGGACUAAUACACCCUUGGAAGUCACUAGAACCCUGGGUAUGCCCCAGACCCUCUAUUGUUUUUUUCCCUCUGAAAGCCAGUGAUUCAUCCUCUAGAGCAGAUUAGACAACUGAGUUUAGGAAAGGUGCCAUGCUCUAAAACGUUGUUAUUCCAAGCUAUUGAGAUUUUUUAAUUAAACUCAAUUUAUUUUGCCACUACCAUAUCUUGGGAGUACCCAAGAAGAAAGUUGAGUAAUAUAAGAACAAACCUUCUGAUAAUUCCUAGCAAGUCACAUUUUCUACAACAGUAUGGGGCCCCAAUAUACUGCAUGGUUAAAUAUAGAACCUGUACCAUUUCUGUGCCAUCUACUCAUUUUUGUGAGUGUGUGUGCCAUCUCCUUCUCUCCCAUCAGCACCGGAAACAUUUGUACAACAACCACUCAAGGUAGUCAUGCCAAAGUUCAGAAGAUAAAGAUCUCUGGAUAUGGUUUUACCUCAACGAACAAAACUAUCCCUUCUCCUUUCCACUUCUCUAAUUCCUACUCAUGUUUCAUUAUACAGCCAGGUUCUACCUAAUGUGAGGAUCCAGAUAAUGUAAAAAGACUCCUUGGAAGCCAUUAAUAUUGUACACUCAUCCUAAGUCUUCUUGCUGUAUCUCAGCUAAGGUCCCAGCUCUAAGGAUACUGUGAUGUAUAGUGUUAAGAUUCUCUUGCUGGAGUGCAGUGGUGCAAUCUCGGCUCACUGCAACCUCCCACUCCCUGGUUCAAGCGAUUCUCCUGCCUCAGCCUCCCAAGUAGCUGGGAUUACAGGCACGCAUCACCACGCCCAGCUAAUUUUUGUAUUUUUAGUAGAGACGGGAUUCACCAUGUUGGCCAGGAUGGUCUUGAUCUCCUGACCUUGUGAUCCACCCACCUCAGCCUCCCAAAGUGCUGGGAUUACAGGCAUGAGCCACCGUGCCUGGCCAGUGUUAAGAUUCUUAAACCAGUAAGUAAAGAAGGAUGACUGAGCAUAGGAGGAAGACUUAGAGGGACCUACUCCACAGAACACUUAUAUUUGUGUUAAGGAGAGAAAACCGACACAAAGCAAAGCAAAGUGAGCAUCCUUCAGGCCUGCUCUUGCACAUCUCCCAGGUAGAGCCUACCCUGACUCCCCAGGGAGCACUCUCAGUACUUCCCUCCUCUUACAUGGUCUUGUGCACAGUGGACUGGUGUCAGGCAUCAACGUGUCUCUCUCCUGCUGGACUAGACACUGCCAAAGAGUAUGCCUUGUUUUUUCCUGUGUGCCCAGCAUCCAGUAUGGUGCCUAGGUCACCCCAGGCAUGCACUGUUCAGUGAGUAAAUGAAGGUGACAGGUAAGGACUGGAGAAGGCAUAGAAGAUAAGACUAGAUCUAGACCACCAAACACAGACUAUCCAUGAGGAAGGAGGACCAGGGCGCGGUCCUGGAAAAUGAACCAGUGGAAGUGAAGACACAAAGUAGAGACUGACCAUGGUGUGUUCAGGAGACAGUGCAGGAAAUGGCUUAAUGGAAGUCAGCAGAUGGAGCAUUUCUGAGUAGCCAAGAGAAAUCUAGAAAGAUGAGCAGGUAGGAAAAAGUAUAGAUGAUCUUAUAAUAAGAGACUCUUUGGAAGUGCUACCAACUGGGAUGUAUCCAGGUAUAUGCACAGAGAAGCGACGUGUGCACUUGAAGCCAAGACUAGCAGGACCUGCAGGAUGGGGGACGGGGGUGGGGCAUGGGGGAAUGGAGAGCUGAGGGCAGGAGAGUUAUGAAGGCCAAGAUCAGGGUGGGAACAGUGUGGAACUAAAGGGAAGAAAUCAGUAGGAGAAGCAACAGGAAGGAAAAACAAAAACGAAUAGGGCAUGGUGACGACUGAUUUGGGGGAUUAGACUGGGGGGGGAAUGAAUUGAGCAAGCCGUUGGCAGCACUUGUUGGAAGCCUUCAGCAUAAAAAUACUGACAGAAUCUACUAAGUUGGAGAUGGGUCUCGUGACCCCAAUGCAAACCAAGUCCAGUCCUGCCUUUAACAUGGGGUGUCUUUUGCUCCAAGCUCAGCUGGGGUAAGCACAGUAGCUGUGUUGCUGGGUUGAGUCCAGGCCACCCUUGGGUCUCAGGCAUUACAUCAUGUCAGACUGCUUCCCAAGAAAGACCACUGAGUCCUCCUCCUCCAGAUUACCAGAGACACUGCCAAGUUUUUCAUGCACAAAGAGAUAAACCUUCGAAGACAUUAGAUGAAACUUUGUGAGGGAAGGAUAUGGUUUCAUGUUUUUAAAAAGUAGCUACUUAUUAUCAUGCACAGAGAAGACAGAGGUUCACAACAGCUGCUGGUCAAGGGAAAAAUUAAACAACCAACUAACCUGGCAGAGUAACACCAGGAUUGAUAAGAGGUAGAUUUUUAAGGAAUAAAAUAUACAGUUUCAAGUAUACAAUAUAUAGACCUUUUGUUUAUUUUCUCUUCACCAGCCCCCCAACAAAAAUGACAUUUUGUGUUAUGAAUGCUAAAAUUUCGCUCUGUGCACACUUGCAAUGAAUAGCUCAUUCAAACCAAGACAGUCUUUUCAGACUAGGCCAUGAACUGCAAACUGUAUGAGGGCCGAGAAGAUUACAAGCACUAACUCUUUCUGCAGACUUCGGUUAGGAUUGUGUACAUGGACCCCAAGUGCAGGUUAUUUUCUCUACAUUUGGCUAUCAGCUUAGGAAUAGAAGCUCAUUACAAGAAAUGCUCAAGUCUCCUUUUCUUCCUGGCACAGCUACCUCUGCAGUGAACCGAAGACCAUGCAAAGUUUAGGAUUUGGCCAAACCAAAGAAACAUUGUGGCAUUUUCAUACUACGAUGAAAAUACAAGAGGGAUCCAUUCUGAUGGUCGAGUUGAUGGGCAUUCCCAUGGCCUUGCCAGAAAGACAGACUGCAUCUUCAACUCUAAAUGACUUCCAUUGUAGUGACCAUUACCUCCAAGCAGAUAUCCUGCCCUGAUUGUCCCAAUAGGGUAUCCUCAAAUAAGACUGGGAAGUGUCAGGGAAAACAGACUCCUUUGAUAUAAGUCAUUUUUAGGGGGGAAAAAAUCAAUGUCCUAGUUUUAGUUUCAGAUAAAUCAUGAGUCAAAACAUGCUGUUUAGUUAAAAAAAAAAAAAAAAAAAAAAAAAGAUUCACCAUAAUCAGGAAGGCAAAGCACUCCCCAAGUACAUUCUAGUAUGUAUCUUUGUGUUUUCAUGUGAGUGAGAUUCCCACUAAGUCUAAAAAAGGGAGACCACCUCUUCUGUGUCCUGCCAACUCCCGCCUCUGAUGGGCCCCAAACUACCAGCUGAUUGUUGCUUCAUCACCAGGAAGCCUCCAGGGUCAGUGGGACACCUGCUAUCGUAACUAAAGGUACUCAUGAGCUGUGUUCAAAGCACAGCCCUCCUGUCUCACACUCUGUCACUGUCAUGAUGAUGGGAAACAGGGAGGCAGGGAAAUUAGUUCCUUUUACCAAUCUCACAGGUGAUUUUGGUGAGUUGUUGGAACCAACUGUACUGAACUCCUUUUGGCCAUUAUUAGCUGGCAUAGCUAACUGCUGCAAAUAAAACUUUUUUUACAUUGACAUAAUGUCUCAUUUCAAGGAGGCAUAUUUUCCAGUUGAUUUUCACCAACAUCAUAAAAUUUUGGUAAUUCAUCUCUAUGAAUGUAGCAGGAUGAGCAAAGGUUAACAUCAACAUAAGCUGAAAAUCAAAGAACUGGGUAGUGAAACAUAAAUUAAAAGUCUGGACCAUUUAAGAGGGCCAUUCCCUGGUUCUUUUAAAACAUGAGCACCAAGCACCAAGCCCCAAGCAUGCAUGCUUGCCCUCCUUUGUUCUCACUCCCCGAAGUAGGCCAGUGUGAGCCUUUGUGGUUUACAUUAUGUGGCUAAAGCAACUGACCAUAGGUUUUUUUGUUCGUUAAGAGUGUUUUCUAAAACCGCAGAUAUGCAUGAGUGGGGGCUGAACCUAAGAUAGGUUUUCUUCUGCCUCGAUGCCUACAUUUAACCUCUGUGAGUGCCCCUUUUCCCUGCUUUGGACUAGGUGGUCAUCAGUUCUUAAUGACAGAGGUUUCACUGCAAUAUUCUACACAUCGAGGGAACGGGGCGUGCCAUCUCCGUGUUUCCUCCAAGGAGCCAUAGUUCUGCAAGAAAACAGUUCCUCACGCAUUGCUCAGUCACACAAGGGUGUCUGAAUUCAUCCAGUCACCCCUUUUUGGUCCUCAUCAGUGACCUCUGCUGAAAACAACAAAUGUAGGGAAAAAAUAACAUUUCACUAUAUAAAGAAAAUUAAACCGGAUAAUGAAUCUAAGACACAGUCCACCAUCUAUGGCAGCUGGCUUUGCCCCAAGGAAAAGAGGACUUCCAGUUCUGAAGACUCAAUUGGCACCUAUGAAACAGGUCUCUAAGUUAACUAUUUCACAAUGUGAGUGACUUCAUUUAGUGAGUGAGGUUCUAUUUUACCUCCCCUUCCGGUGGAAGCCGGUGGUGAAGAAUGGGAUGUUCAUUUUCACCAUUCUCCCAUUCUGAGUAGCCUCAUGUUCAGGCACCCCCUUGGCAUAUGGAAGAAAAUGCUGACCCAGUUCAUCUUGAAUCCCCACCAGCAUCUUUGACUCCAAGGUGUCUGAACAGUGAGAAAGCCACUAGGAAAACCCAUAAUUUCAUACAAUCCCUUGUGGCACUCCUCUGACUGCUUGCCUAGCUAUCUUACUAUAUGCGGAGACUGCUGGGCCCUGGGAGGUGUCUCGGUCAGACUGGCAGCUGCCUGCAUCUUCCCCCACAAAUCCCAUCACAGGGUCAAACUGCAAACCUGCAAAUCAGCACGGACAUUUUAAGAAUGGACAGAAUCCAAUGGAGAGUUUCUCUUGGCAGCUAAUGGAACCCCACAAAAUUGCCUUCAGACUAUUGAGUCUGUUUUAUUUCUAAUUAAAACAGAUGCUAACUUCCUUCCUUACAGUACGUUUGCUCAAAUAUUGACAUAUCUUCUGCUAAACAUUUAACUAUACAUAGCCAAAUACAUACGCAGGCACGUAUAUACCUAUGCAUAUAUACAUACAUAUACACACUUGAAAUUCAUUUUCAUUCUUUAUCAGGGCUCCCUCAAAACAAUAAAAGAUGACCUUUGACAAAUUACUUAUAGCCCCAUCUCAUCAUUUCUGGGUUUUUCUUAUUCUGAUACUAGUGGUUAUGCCUUCCAGAGGCCUGCUUCAGGUGUGGAUUAGAUUUUACCUUGUGUUAUUUUCAUUGGCAAAACCAGAACGACGCUGUACCUCCCUCCAUUCUCCCCAAAUUGGAAAACAGAAGGAAAAAUAAAUCUCUCCGAAUGUGCUAUCUUAAUACCACAACGAUGACCGUUUUUGUUCAUUUUUUUCCAGUAUAAUCUGUAGACUGCUUUGUUUCACUUAACAUUAUUUCGUGUUUUUCUAUGAUACUAAAUAAUCUCUAUAAUUAUCCUUUUAAUGGCCGCCCAGAGUGAAUGUAAACCAUAAUUUACUUAACUGUUUACCUAUUGUUAGCCAUUAAGUUGCUUCCAUUUUUCACUUAUUUAAGUUGGAAUGCACAUUUUCAUAUCAGCCAUUAAUUUAAAGCAGCAUGCAGAGAUGGUUCUCCGUCACUAAUCUAAAAAUGCAGGGUUUAUGUAUUUACAGCUCACUUUGAUUAUGAAAUUUAAUUUGAGGGUAAUUAAGACAUUUAUAUUCCAAACAGCUCCUCGACAUCUAGCUCUCUCGAGCCAAACAGGCACAACCAUGACUAGCCAUUUUCACCUCAAGACAGCACAGUCCAAUGAAUUCUAAAACACAAUUUUCUUACGAAAAAUAAACUUUAUGAACUCCUGCUGCUUUAGAGCCAAGAGAUCAGCUCCCCAAACCAGAGUCCAUGGUUCUCUAGGGUGACCCAGCCAAGGCAAGCCAUCAUGAAGAAUCCUAUUGCAGCUUCAUGCUCAGUCCAGAAUUCAAGGCAACAUUCACUCAGUGCUCCAACACCCACUGUGUUACCGGAACUACCUGGAUGUCCUUGCCUAACCAGCACCCAGAUACACUGUGGGAACAAGACAAGGGCAUUGCUCAGAUGAGUUUCAGUUGUUUGAUGUUUUCAAGUUUAUCAUGGAUCACUUCAAGUUACAGAGUUCCUUGAGCAGGGGUAGUGGGUUAGGGCAUGUGAUUCAAACGGAUUCAGCUGUUUCAAUGGGUGUGGCCCACUAGCCUCCUCACUCUGAGCAAGUUGCAAAAAAUCCCAAAAUCGUGUGCCUCGGUUUCUCAAUCUGCAGUAUGAGGGUAUCAAUAGUGGCUGCCUUGUAAGGAUAUGAUGAGGAUCAAAUCUAGAAAACACAACUGCUAUGCAUAGGGGAAUGGUGACAUUUGAUUAGCACAUAGGAGCACUUAACUGCAUGCUUACUGAAUGUUAAUGCUACACUGUAACGUAUGUACAUUCACUUGCUGAAUAAAUGCAUGAAGGAAUGAUGAAUGAAAUAGUGUGGGAGAAGGUUCCACUUGUCUUAGGGAAAGUCCUCUGUAGAAUGCCCCAUUUCCUUUCAUAACAAAAUCAUUUUCUUAAUGGUAAUCACUGUAAGCCUUACCCUCCACCCCCAAUAAAGAGCAAAUGAACACCCCGAAAAGAUGUGUCCACCUUAGUAAUUCUUAAUGUCCAGAAAUUCAAUUUUAAAGCUUUAGAAAAUGUCAUCCAGCCGUCAGAAAGAACUCAUAACCUCAUUUGAAGCCAAAAUAAACCAGCCACAAAAAUUCCUUGGUGUUUUCCCUAUCAGAGAAUAAGAACUCAAUUACUAUUACUGUUUUUUAAGUCAGCAAUAACAAACUAAAGUGAUUAAAAAUCCUAAGUAUUACCAUCAUUUUUUUACUAACAACGAAAUGAUUUUUAUGUACCAGCAACCCUCUAUAAAACAGAGAAGAGCUUAGAAUUUUUUAUUAUUAUUUGGCCACCAGCAAUUAAUUCUUCUGAUUUGUUGUAUUAGUUUGAUGGUUGCGUCCAAGACCUAGAAUAUUUCUUACCCCAGCCAACUGAUGUAAGAAAAUUAUUUCAGUGCAGUCCCUAGCAAAUGGUGAUGAUGAAUAGCAUGGCAGGACAAACUUAUUCAGACACACAUUUUUCAGAAGUAGCAGGGAAAAGGCUGAUAAAUUACUAGUAAAUUGCUUUUUGUAAAAAUGCUCUCUCUUUCAAAUUUUCCCUAGUAUGAAGGUCUUCUGCAGAAUGAUGGCACAAUACAUUCUGACAUACCUGGACAACAAAGGCAGUUAAAGAAUGAAUAGGAGAUCAGAGUGAAGAAUUAUUUUCCAGUACCACUCUCCAUGGAAUAAAAGGAGUUGCAAACAUGGCCUUUGUAGAUGCAGGGAAACCCACGUUCCUUUUAGAGCUGAUGUUAACCCAUGAGAAGCGACCACCCCUCGACGACUUCUCCUUCACGGUUCCCACCCAGGAGCACGGCCAACUCUCCCCCGGAAUCCAUAACGGCUCACGCAAAUAGAUUUCUUUCCGUUCCUCCUCGGAGGGCUCUCCACAUUUAUCUGCUCGAGACGUGGCAGCUCCAGAACCAUGGUCAGUAAGGACACCGGCAAAUGCAUACUCACAACGUCGGAGAGUGAAGUGGAACCCGCCGCCUGCCUGGCCCUGGAGAUGAAAUACGCCCUGGACCCCAACCGGCAGAUUAAAAAACGGAACAAAGCCCUGCAGGUGCGGUUUAAGGAUAUCUGCGAGGCACAGAAUGAGCAGAGGGACACACAGCUGUCCUCGGGCCAGCUGGGGGAGAAGCGGGAGGCCAAGCCCGUGUCCUGCAGAGCAGCCUACCGCAAAUACAUGACAGUGCCCGCACGCAGGUCCAUCCCCAACGUCACCAAGAGCACAGGCGUGCAGACCUCGCCCGACCUUAAGAAGUGUUACCAGACGUUCCCUCUGGACCGCAAAAAGGGGAACCUCAAAAGCCUCCCAGCUGCAGAUCCCUUUAAAAGCCAAAACAAUGGGUUUCUAACAGAUGCGAAAGAGAAGAACGAGGCUGGACCCAUGGAGGAGGCCCGGCCAUGUGGCGCGGGGCGGGUGCACAAGACCACAGCCUUGGUUUUCCAUUCCAACCAACACAUGAACACAGUGGACCAGCCUUUGGGGGUCAACUGCACAGAGCCCUGUAAAAGCCCGGAGCCGCUCAGCUAUGGAGAAGCUGCGCUCCAAAACUCCACUCGGCCUCCAUCCGAAGAGCCCGAUUACCAGCUGCUCGGGAGGGCCAAGCAGGACCGGGGGAGGCCAAACUCCGAGGAGCCCGCUCCACCUGCCCUCAGGAGGGUGUUUAAAACGGAGGUUGCCACCGUUUACGCACCUGCCCUCAGUGCCAGGGCCCCCGAGCCUGGUUUGUCAGACUCUGCAGCCGCCAGCCAGUGGUCACUCUGCCCGGCAGAUGACGAGCGGAGGAGAGCCACACAUCUCAACGGGCUCCAGGCGCCCUCGGAAACUGCCCUGGCCUGCUCACCCCCGAUGCAGUGCCUGUCCCCCGAAUGUAGUGAGCAGCCGUCGCAGACUCACACCCCGCCGGGGCUGGGGAACCAGCCUAGUCCCACAGCGGUUGCUGCAGGUGAAGAAUGCCAACGAAUCGUGCCUCAUACGGAAGUGGUCGACCUCAAAGCACAACUUCAGAUGAUGGAGAACUUGAUCAGUUCAAGCCAAGAAACCAUCAAAGUGCUCUUGGGGGUCAUUCAGGAGUUGGAAAAAGGAGAGGCCCAUCGGGAAGGGUAUGUAUGUUCACCCAUGUCUUAGGAAGCUAUGCAGGCUGAUCACCACAGAGUCCAUCUGUAGCCCCAAACCCAAGUCUGUAAUGAGACUAAAGCCAGCAUUUCCGUAAACAGGUCAUAGUCUAAGGGCGUGGCGAGCUCCAAGGGGUCGCAGAUUAUUUUAUGAUACUAGACGUCACUGCAUCCUGCACGAUACGCUUUCUGGUUAAUGUUCAUCUUUCUGGCCUUGAAUUCAAACCAUACCUAUGCUUAGAAUGAAUUGAUAGACCUUUCCUUUUAUUCUGCUAGGGCUAAAGGUUUAUGAUAUUGAUAAUGUAUAACAACAUAUGCCAGUCCAAAAUAUCUAUUCUAAAUAAGAAGAGAAUCAGGAAGAGAAGAGGCCACAGGCCUCUUAGGAAUCGUAUUAGGAAGAGAAAGGAAAUUUCAUGUGACAUUUGGAAAAGUAAAUGCUGACUUGCUUAUAAUAAAUAAUUGAAAUAAUAUUGGUAUUCAGGACUGUACAAGGCUUUACAUCAUAGACAGUGUGUUUUCCAUUCUGUACCUGGAACCCAAAGAAGCAAUGGGCAUUGUGAGACCAGUCCUGACUGUAUAUGAUUAGGAGACAGAUGCCCUUCCCCACGGGCUGCCCUAUGUGUCCAGUGGGGCUGCAGAAAGAAUGAUACUAACUUCACGGCCAAUACUUUAUUGCGUUGAUAAGACCAUCUUGCACUUCAUGUUUUGAAGUUUAAACUGUGCAGCAGCAUCUUUAAAAACAAAUGACCUAAAGGUGGGGUUUUAGUUCUUGAGCUCCCCAGUGCGGAAGCCUCCUACAGGCCGGCAUGUGCUCAGCUGAUACAAAGCAGCCUGUUCUACUCUGGGUCUGGGGGUUAUCGGACUUCGCCUGGAUUGCCGAGACCUCUCUUGCCCAUUGCCCCUUGAAAGUGUCUGUGUUCCUGCUAGCCUGUGUACUGGAGGUAACAUCGGAGGCAGCGCCCUGUUGCCUCAUGUGAUGUGCACCCUUCACUCUGCGAGCCCUGAGCCCUGGGUUUAGCAAGCUAGAAGCCAGCCUGAAAUAAGCCAAGUAAUGUAUUUCCAGGACAGAAAACCACCUGGGCACAAAGUUUCCUUAAGAGGAUUGCUGUGGCUGAGUUAGACAGUUUGCUGACUGCAAAGAAUGGGGAGGAAACACCUCCUGCCUUAAGGUGGAGGCUGAGGUGAAAGGCCCAGCUCCAGCAGUGGAGAGGCUGGGGCAGGUCCUGCCCUGGGCUCUGGCUGCUCCAGCUUGGUGCAGGAGGCCUGUCUACAGCUUGAUGCUCUUAAGCAAAAAGAACUGCCAGCCAAAUGUACAAAAAUCUUAACAGUAGAUUCAUAGGUAAUCUAACACCAUAUAACAUUUCCAAAAGGCCUUGUUCAAUCUUGGGUUUACAUCUCCAUUUUCAUCCCAUUUCCAUCAGUACAGAUCCAAAAGCAACACUCAUCAGGCGUGGGGUGGGGGAGACCAGUGAUUUACUGAUCAGUAGUCCACAUUCCUGCAAAAAAAUUAAAAGGUCAAACAUUGACCCAGUCACUGAUGUUGAUAUAGUUGGUAGUGAAUUAAACCAGACAGCAAAAGAGAAAGAUGCCAACAUCUUUGGUGAAAUAAAGUUCACCAAAUGGUGUAAAAUGAAAUAUGUACACUAAUGUGCAUACUCACAGGAGUGUGUGCCCAAAGAAGAACCUGAGAGGGCUGAACACCCACGAACACAAGAAAGGAAAACCGUACGAUAUAUGGGAGCGCCUUCUUACACUCCUCUUAGAACAAGUAUGGAAGAUUGCUUUAAAUAAGAUCCUCAGGGUUCUCUGAGAUGCCAUCCAUCUAGCAGUGUGGUUCUCAGUUUACUAAGACAUGUCUGGGUAGGAAUCUGGCACUGAGGGCUUGGGCAAGGGCUGUAUGUCUCUGUGCCUUCUUUCUUCACCUGUAAGUUGAGAUCACUGUCUGUCCUGCAGACAGGGGAUGGAAUGACAUGGGGUGACCUUCUAAUGUGUUCAGCCUAGUGGCAGGUGUGUCUGAAUGGGUAGAUGUCCACUAGUGGCAUGAGUGUUGAUCUUGCUGGCCAGCAAUGCUGGAGCAGGGGUCUGGGGAGGACUUAGUGGUCUUGUGGGCGUCCAAUGUGAUGAAUGCAUCCCCUAUAUGCCCGGCACACAGGCUGCCACACAAGACUGUCCCUGAAACUCUGGAGCUGCUCUAUCCAAUACAGUGGCCACUAGCUGCACGUGGCUAUUGAAAUUCAAACUCAAUGACAAUUGAAACUUCACAGUCACAGCAGUCACAUUUCAAAUGCUCGAUAGCCACAUACAUAAGACAGUGCAGCUACGGAACAUUUCCAUCAUCACGAAAUGUCAUUCACUCCGGUAUCCCAGAACAUGGCACAGUGCCUGGUUCUUAAGCAUCUGAGGACUUGGGCACCUUAAAUCAAGACAAAGGAUGGUUUUACUUUAAAAUCAAUCCUAGUUCAGUUGCUGCCAGCACAAGCUCACGGUGGAAGGUAGAAAGGCAGGUCUCUGUUGUGUUCCUGGGAACAUUCACUUCCUCUCUCUCAGAGCCCUCUGGACUCAGAUAGCAAAGAAUCAAGUGCCACCUUAUGGGCUCCAAAAUUCAAGGCCACCUUAUGGGGCCCCCUCUUGCUCAAUGCCCCAGGGUCAUUAAUUUGGCUGAAAUUCAAAUUUCCCACCCGUCUUCUCCAUGUCAGAACAUAGGAGAGGACUGCAGCCUCAGAGACAGGCAGAUAAGAUGCAAGCUCAUUCUCCAUCCCUUCCCAGACCCUGGGUACAGCACAGAGUCCCAGGAGUGACAGCUGUGAGCAGUGGCAGCCAGCACUGGGCUGGGACAUCUGGAACAACAGGCUCUGGAGGGAAGGGAAGUAGCAUCUGCUGAUUUCCAUGGUGUAAAUACUGCUACCGUGGCCAAUUUCAAUCUCAUGAAAUCCUAAAAAUGUAACACUCUGCUCCACUCAGCACCCAACCAAUCCCUUGAAGGGCAAGUUCUAGGACUUUAGAACGAGGGAUUCACAGGGCUUACUUUAUGUACCAGAUCUGAACUGGGAAGUUGGUAUUUUAGUUGCAUCUCAUGGUUUAAAAAAACAAACAAACAAAAAAAGAAAACAGGAAAAUGCACUCUGUGUACACUGAUACAUAGUUAUUAUAUGAUACGACAAUGAACUCAAAUGACCAAGUUAAAAUAUCAGUGGAGGCCGGGCACGGUGGAUCAUGCCUGUAAUCCCAGCACUUUGGGAGGCCAAGGCGAGUGGAUCACUUGAGGUCAGGAGUUUGAGACCAGUCUGGCCAACAUGGUGAAAUCCCGUCUCUACUAAAAAAUACAAACAUUAGUCGGGCGUGGUGGCGGGCACCUGUAAUCCUAGCUCCUCCAGAGGCUGAGGCAGGAGAAUUGCUUGAACCCGGGAGGUGGAGGUUGCAGUGGGCCAAGAUCACACCACUGCACUCCAGCCUGGGCAACAGAGCGAGACUCCAUCUCAAAAAAAUAAAAAUAAAAUCAAUGGAACUUUUCUUGGAAAAUAUUCUAAAGCCUACAAAUCAGGAGCUGGAGAACACUCUUGAAGCUGGGGAAAGUCAGUUCCUCUCCCCACUUGCCACCCCAAUAAAGCAUACAGGGGCUUCCAACAGAAUUUCAUCUGCAUUCAGAAGAGUCCUAGUGAGGGCAGGCACCUCGGAGCCCAUGAGUUUGAAUACAAGUGACAAAUCUUGCCCCCACAUUUCCACACUAUACUUAAGGUCUGACCUGGCCCAAAGGGGUCAUGGGCCUGCUCCUUGGGAAGCCAGUAUUCUUUGAAUCCCGCUGAUGGCCCUGGGCAAUGUAUGUUUCUUAGAACAUGUUUAUUGUAAAAUCUCUUUAAUAGGACUUCUUUUCACUAUUGAGUUUGUCAGGCAAGUGCUUCCCUGUAGUUCUUAACCUGUGCAGGAAUUUCUGUGUCACUGGCUACAACCGCUCUCAGUAGCUUCCAAAUUAUUUUUCGUAAGAGACUCUCCUUCAUUAUUUUCAUUUGCUUAUGUAGAUUUCCAAAUGGCUUCGGCAGAGAAUGUUUAUGGCUGAGACAGGUUAACCUCUGUGAGCUUCAAUUUUGUCUGAAAUCAACUAGGGGUGGUAGACACUGAAAUACAGUAUCUACAAAGCUCCCACUUAUAACCAGCACACAGUUGGCGCUGAAUAAAGGACAUAUCCUGUUACGAGCAUUUCAGUGGGAUGAAUUCUGCAAGUAGGUUAGAUGUGCAAAAAGUAUGCAAAAUCACGCCUUUUAGUCCCUUGUAAAACACUGGGGCAAUUCACUAAAAUCACUCUGCUUUAUGCAGUGCGGGCUUGCAUGAAUGCCAAGAAUUAUCCUGCUUAUUUCAGAGCUCUUAGUAUUAUGCUUGUGUCUUCUGGGGAAGUUCAGGGUCACACAGGCUACCUAAAUAAGUCACUAAUGGGAGUCAUUGAAGGCUAAGAACAAGGCAAAUGGGACAGUGGAUUUAAAAAACCCAAUCAAUUAUUAGAACAGUGCUAAUUCACUGUAGCAGCUAUGGGAUUCCUGGGCAGGAGAUCCUCAGACCAAUGGGGUGUAGGUCUUGGUGGCUCAUUGGGUAAACUCACCAGCAACUACAGUGUGGCAACCCCGACAGCGCUCUUUGCCUCUUAGAUUUCCUACGCCAAACAUUUAGUCUCUUGAAGUGUCCAUUGGCUGGUGACAGCCUAAUGAUACUCUGCUAUUUGGAGAAGACCAGAAAUGAUCGUGAGAAGCUUUACUUGAGGAUAUCAAGCACAUGAUCAGAAUCUGUCACUGCCCAGAGUGAAGCAGAUUCUUCUAUGGGCCAGGCCUCCCUCAGCAUUUGCUGGGUGUUACCUGCAGGCUUGGGGUAGGGGGAGAGAGCAAGAGGACCCCAGGCCCUUAAACAUGACCAGCAGGUAGUGAUAAGACCCUGAGGCUUCGGGGCUUUGUGACUUUACUAAUUCAGAGCAAAGGCAAGAGUAUGAUUAAAAACAGAAAAUCCUAAGUAACACACCAACCCAAAGAGUCUAGUACCUUGCAGGAAGGGUGGCAAACCCAGUCAUUUAUCACCUCCCAUCAUCCCUGCCACCCCAUCAUGGGGGCAGUUCCCUGUCAGCAGGGGUUCUGUUCAUCCUCAUUGAGAAAGGGUGGUUUCUUGGUGGUGUGAGGCCAGCUCUCCCAAGUCUCGGGCACACAGUGGUAAAAAAAGAAGCUAAAGGAACCCCCUGAGUUCAGGGGCUCUGUGAGGGUGCCGCUUACGGUGGUGUUCAAGACAAGGGAGAGAGGAAGAAAGAGCUGAGGGAUGGAACGAGUUAAUACAGACGAAGUGUGGUAUCCUGUACCAAGGUUUGCUCAACUUUACCAAAAACAAUGAAUAGCCAACAAGUAAUGGAAGGUCAUGUGCACAUACACAUACUUAAGAGGUAAGGACUUAGUCUCAUGGACAUCUGUGUUUACUGCAGGGGCUCAGGGUCAGCUCCUACAUGGCAGAGGUCAGCAAACUUUUCUGCAAAGGGCCAAAUAGUAAAUACAUAUUGACAGCCAGUCUUUGUCACAAUGAUUCAACUCUGCCAUUGUAUCCUGAAAGCACCCACAGAGAAUCUGUAUGAAUGGGCAUACUUGUGUUCCAAUAAAACUUUAUUUACAAAAACAGGUGGUAGCCAGAUUUGGGCCACAAGCCAUAGGUUAUGGACUCCUGAUAUAUGGUUUGUAAAUACAGUGACCAUAUUCAUACAGCUAAAAAUGUUCAGGCCAGAAUAUGGGUGCAGGCAGUCCAAGGUGUGUGACUGCCAAGCACACCGGCCUAUCAUUCAUUCACACAUUUAGAAGGUUUCUGCCAAACAUCACUGAAGUGAUGGACACUGUGCCAGGCAAUGAGGGGAUGUGAGAGUCAAAGGAAUUCGGGCCCAGCCUUUGAGGGGUUCACAGUUCAUCGGCAUUCAGGCUGUUCAAAUAUACGCUUAAUUGUUCAUCAGCCCAUACAACCUGGGGUCCUGCUUUGGAACUCUGUGUGUGUAUGACACACAUAUACCUAAUAUGUAUGUAUAAUGUAUAUGACAGCAUCUCUUGGAAACAUGAAAAAGGUCUCAUUCUCCCAGCAGCAGAAAUAAAAAGCCAUCACAGAA